ACUGCCGCUGCGGCUGUUGCUGCGGAGCCAGGAGGGGAAGCGAUGGCUGGGCCCGCGUGGAUCUCUAAGGUGAGCGCUGGCAGGCCGGCGUGUGGCAGGCAGGCAGGCCGCGAGGGCUGGCAGGAGAGCCGGUCGCGUGCCGGGUGUGGGCGGGCGCGUGGGCCAGACAGGGAGGCGGUGGCUGCCCGCGGGGACAGCUUGGGAGCCGGUCCUGGUCGCCCGUGCCCCGCGCUCCGUGGCCGGCUCGCAGUGUAUGGGCCGCCCCGGGCCGGGUCAGCAGCGCAGAGGCGGGGACGGCGUCAAGGUCAAGGCGGGGGGGCGCCGGCCCUGCUCCUGCCGAGACCCGGCUGCCGUCACCCGCAUCCGCCCAGGCCAGAGCCCAGGCUUCGCGCCGAGCCCGGGAAGGUCACGGGAGCCUCUGUCCCGGCUCCGCCAUCCGGGCCGCUUCCCCGGCUGCGGCCCUGCUGCGGGACUGAUCCCCUCAGCACUGCCCACACCUCUCAUCCGCUGUCUGCGCGGCCCUUGGCCGGGGAACCGCAGGUGCCACGGGCACUGGCGUUGAGCUUGGGAGGUUUUCCCAGGUCUCUCGGCUGCUGGGGGCAUUCCACAACCCAAAACAGGUGACCAGAGGUUUUACUGGUGGUAUCAACUUUGCCAAGCUUAUGUAGAUUACUCUUAGAUUUAAGCAGACAGUUUUAUAGAGGAACUAAGAAAAAAAUGGAAGCUCUCUUGAUAAAAAGUCUGAUUUUCCCUGAGUACCAAAACAGACCUCAGUAAUAUUUUGGAAAUGUGUCUGAAAAUGUUUUGCAAGACUGAAGAAGUUGCAUGAGAAGCUUUCCAGGAUCACAAUGGAAAGGAAAGGAAAACACUUGCCUUCAUGAGAAACCGUCUAAAUUUUAGUUCAGACAGUAACUUUAAUUCCAGGAGAUGGUAUUGGCCCAGAAAUUUCAGCUGCAGUUAUGAAGAUUUUUGAUGCUGCCAAAGCACCUAUUCAGUGGGAGGAGCGGAACGUCACUGCCAUUCAAGGACCUGGAGGAAAGUGGAUGAUCCCUUCAGAGGCUAAAGAGUCCAUGGAUAAGAACAAGAUGGGCUUGAAAGGCCCUUUGAAGACCCCAAUAGCAGCCGGUCACCCAUCUAUGAAUUUACUGCUGCGCAAAACAUUUGACCUUUACGCGAAUGUCCGACCAUGUGUCUCUAUCGAAGGCUAUAAAACCCCUUACACCGAUGUAAAUAUUGUGACCAUUCGAGAGAACACAGAAGGAGAAUACAGUGGAAUUGAGCAUGUGAUUGUUGAUGGAGUCGUGCAGAGUAUCAAGCUCAUCACCGAGGGGGCGAGCAAGCGCAUUGCUGAGUUUGCCUUUGAGUAUGCCCGGAACAACCACCGGAGCAACGUCACGGCGGUGCACAAAGCCAACAUCAUGCGGAUGUCAGAUGGGCUUUUUCUACAAAAAUGCAGGGAAGUUGCAGAAAGCUGUAAAGAUAUUAAAUUUAAUGAGAUGUACCUUGAUACAGUAUGUUUGAAUAUGGUACAAGAUCCUUCCCAAUUUGAUGUUCUUGUUAUGCCAAAUUUGUAUGGAGACAUCCUUAGUGACUUGUGUGCAGGAUUGAUCGGAGGUCUCGGUGUGACACCAAGUGGCAACAUUGGAGCCAAUGGGGUUGCAAUUUUUGAGUCGGUUCAUGGGACGGCUCCAGACAUUGCAGGCAAGGACAUGGCGAAUCCCACAGCCCUCCUGCUCAGUGCCGUGAUGAUGCUGCGCCACAUGGGACUUUUUGACCAUGCUGCAAGAAUUGAGGCUGCGUGUUUUGCUACAAUUAAGGACGGAAAGAGCUUGACAAAAGAUUUGGGAGGCAAUGCAAAAUGCUCAGACUUCACAGAGGAAAUCUGUCGCCGAGUAAAAGAUUUAGAUUAACACUUCUACAACUGGCAUUUACAUCAGUCACUCUAAAUGGACACCACAUGAACCUCUGUUUAGAAUACCUACGUAUGUAUGCAUUGGUUUGCUUGUUUCUUGACAGUACAUUUUUAGAUCUGGCCUUUUCUUAACAAAAUCUGUGCAAAAGAUGCAGGUGGAUGUCCCUAGGUCUGUUUUCAAAGAACUUUUUCCAAGUGCUUGUUUUAUUUAUUAAGUGUCUACCUGGUAAAUGUUUUUUUUGUAAACUCUGAGUGGACUGUAUCAUUUGCUAUUCUAAACCAUUUUACACUUAAGUUAAAAUAGUUUCUCUUCAGCUGUAAAUAACAGGAUACAGAAUUAACAAGAGAAAAUGUCUAACUUUUUAAGAAAAACCUUAUUUUCUUCGGUUUUUGAAAAACAUAAUGGAAAUAAAACAGGAUAUUGACAUAAUAGCACAAAAUGACACUCUUCUAAAACUAAAUGGGCACAAGAGAAUUUUCCUGGGAAAGUUCACAUCAAAAAGAGUGAAUGUGGUAUAUUUCUAAAUGAUAUGGAAAAUAGAGACAGAUUUGUCCUUUACAGAAAUUACUGAGUGUGAAUAAAAACUUCAGAUCCAAGAAAUAUAUAAUGAGAGAUAUAAUUUUUGUUAAUAAGACAAAGGUAAUAUAUUGGAUACAAAGACACAAAUGUAUUGUGUGUUCAAUUAUUUUGUUGUCUUGAGAUUUAAUAUUCUUUCCAAGAGCUUUUAAUGAAGCAGAGAGCUAGUACUUCAUUUUCACUGGAUACAUUUUCAGCAUCAUGAGUUGUCACAGCCUCUGAGCCCCUGAUCUGAAGCCAGAAGGGCUGAGUGUAUUGUAAACUUAUUCUUGCAUGUUGCUGUCUGGGAAUGGACCACACUACAGCAGGUAGUUCUGGGGGCGAUACUGCCGAAAGGCCCGAACACAUGUAUUUUGGCUGCAAUUGAGGAACUUGGGAUGCUAUUAAUUUUGUAUUUCAGCAACUGCCCCUUCUCCUAUCCCAAAGCACCAAUUACUGCCCUCUGCCUCAGCAGUACCAGUAUAAGAUGACAUUCCAAAGACUGGAGGCAACUCAGCCUGAGUUAAUUCACAAAAUUAUGCCAUGCUGGGGCUUGAGCUUGAGCUUGGGCUUAGGCUUGGGCUCAGCUUUUGACCCUCAGGCAUCUCCUUUCCCUUCCUGUCUUCCUCUCCCUUCUCCUCUGCUGCAGCAUGAUUUUCUUAAUCUUCAGACACUCACUAUUUUCAUGAACAGUUACCCUCUGUCCCCACAACCAAAGACAACUCAUGGCCUCCUUUGGCCCUUGUGUAACAUUGCAAACCUGUGGCUUUGCAAAAUGUACCCAGGUCACAAGGGGAUUUUUUUUUUUUUAGCAAUGAUAUCCCUGUCUGGGUCACUUUUUAAGCUUGUAACCGCCCCCCCAGACUUAUAAUCUUAAAUGUAUUUUCCUUUGUUUAAGCUGCUGCUUCCUCUGUUUCAUUGGAUUGUGCCAGUUAUCAGUGGCUCUUGGGUUCAAAGUAAUAAAGAAUUCCAAAACUGAGAUGUUUGCUUUCUCUACCUGUUUCCUGUUCAGAUGCCUUCGGUCAUUUUGGCUCAGCUUGCUACUGAGAAUGGCUGCUUCCCGUAUUCAGAAUGGAAGUGGGGUGGUCUGGUGGCGACAGGCUAACGUAGAGCUGGCUGCUUUUAUGAGAAUGCGCCACUUGACCCCAUCCUGCACCUUUGUUUAUUCCAGGGCACUAAUGGUCACUCGCAUGCCCGCUGUGCACAGUCCUGUGAGUUAAAUGCCCACUACUCUCUGCACUGGUCCCACCUGCUCAAUUGACAAAAAAAAUCAGGUCCUUGUUGACAGUUCUGUUAAAAGGUUUAAUAUUCAAAUUAUACAUUAAAUAGAAUCAAACAGGCAGCAGCAGUUUUAUUAAGCAUCAAGUCAGUUGGCAUGUGGGUGGCGGAGUGCCUGGUAAUGGAAUAAUAGGGUCGGCGAUGCCCGCCAAGAUUCCAGAGUAAGUCAGGUCGCUAGGUGAGUUGUGACUGAUUGCUUUUCCUGCAGCGCACGUGAGCAGUAUCAGCCAUCUCUCUCCUACCCGCUCCACAGCCUACUGCUGGCUGUCCUGUAUGUGAGCUAGCAGCUUUUUAAUCUACCUGGAACUAAGGCCAAAAAUUAUCAGCCCUUUCGUUCUGGAAGGAGAGCUGAUCUCAUUUGUCACCUGAACAAAAAGCAAUACUUAAACUGAAUUAAAACUACCCACACGUGAAGCUUCUUGGAAUUGUCAGCUAUUGUUGGCGUAAGACCUGGUAAAUGUAGAGCCAGUGCUGUGCCCUGACCUGGAGAUCUAACAGACUUGGCAGAAAUGCCUGUGCCCAGACUGAAGAGACCUGGGGCUCAGGAAGAGGCUCGGAACGCCUGCCCUCUAUUCUAUAGAAACUGCAGGCAUAGGCCCUGAUUACAUUUUUUGCUCUUGGUAAAAGGAGUCAAUGAUACCUUUGUACUUCUCCAAAACUGUGAGCCGUUUCAGUUUCAUCGUGGGACCUAAAAGGGAAAUGAGAAGAAAUGAGUGAGGCCCAGGCUCUGAGAACUCUGAGAAUGUGUGUGGUAAAGACUCACACUCAGUCCUAUAUAUAACUCAGGAAUUAAGCCAGAUAAUCAGGACCGUCAGUAGCCAGCCUCCAAGACAGUGAUCGCUCCUGGUAUUCAUAUGGCUUGUGUGUAGUCUCCUGUGUUAUACCACUGGUUGUGGCCAGUGGAGUAUAGAUGAAGGGUUGGUAUGUCACCUCUGAGAAUAGGUUAUAAAAGAUCAGUUUCUUUUAUACACAUAGGAAAGUAGUGUAAGCUACAUCUGCCUUUUCCUUGACCUGUACCCAGUUUUGACCCUCAGUCCAUUUUCUCUGAAAUGGAUUUAUUUGUUCCAUCUCUUGAAUGAAUAAAUUGUUGAAGCAAUUAAAAAA